GCGGUCUGAGAGACCGGUUCACGUGCAGGCAGCGGCGGAUCAUAUUCCUUCAUCUACCAUGGCUCAGCCGGGAACUCUGAACCUCAAUAACGAGGUUGUGAAGAUGAGAAAAGAAGUGAAGAGAAUUCGAGUUUUAGUUAUCCGAAAACUUGUCAGGAGUGUUGGCCGACUGAAGUCAAAAAAGGGUACUGAAGAUGCACUGUUAAAAAACCAAAGACGGGCGCAAAGAUUGCUUGAAGAAAUCCAUGCCAUGAAGGAAUUGAAACCUGACAUAGUAACUAAAUCUGCUCUUGGUGAUGAUAUCAACUUUGAAAAAAUCUUCAAAAAGCCAGAUUCUACUGCAACUGAAAGAGCAAUUGCCAGACUAGCAGUACAUCCUCUUCUGAAGAAAAAGAUAGAUGUGCUAAAAGCUGCUGUACAAGCCUUUAAAGAAGCAAGACAAAAUGUUGCUGAAGUUGAGUCAUCAAAGAAUGCUUCAGAGGACAAUCAUUCUGAGAAUACUUUGUAUUCAAAUGAUAAUGGAAGUAAUUUACAGCGUGAAGCAACUGUCAUCAGUGAGCAAAAAGUCAAAGAAACCAAAAUAUUGGCGAAGAAACCAAUACAUAAUUCAAAGGAAAAAAUAGCAAAGAUGGAACAUGGACCUAAAGCAGUGACUAUUGCAAAUUCUCCAUCAAAGCCUUCAGAAAAGGAUUCUGUAGUUUCCCUUGAGUCCCAGAAGACACCUGCUGACCCAAAACUGAAAACUCUAAGUCAAACCAAAAAAAACAAAGGAUCUGAUAGCUCACUCUCUGGUAACAGUGAUGGCGGAGAAGAAUUUUGUGAAGAGGAGAAGGAAUAUUUUGAUGAUAGCACAGAAGAAAGGUUUUACAAGCAGUCUUCCAUGUCUGAAGAUAGUGAUAGCGGUGACGACUUCUUCAUUGGGAAAGUCAGACGGACACGAAAGAAGGAAAGUAGUUGUCAUUCUUCAGUUAAGGAACAAAAACCACUAGAAAAAGUGUUUCUUAAAGAAGAUACAGGUGAAACUCAUGGGGAUACAAGAAAUGACAAAAUCAAGCCAAGUACAGAAACCAGAAAGUUAGAAUCAGUGUUUUUCCACUCUUUAUCUGGAUCUAAAAGCUCUAGAAGAAAUUUCAAAGAACAGGCUCCAAAAACAAGAUCCCUAGGUAAGAAAUAAGACUUGCAUUUGUGAUAUCAAAAAUCACCUGAGAAAUGAAAAGCAACCCAAAAGUACCCAGGAGGCCCAUUUACUUACUGAUGACAACUGUGCCAUUCCCAGGAAUAUCUUGGUCGGCUGGGUAAGAAAUCUGAUGUCCCUUGGUUUUUCACUCUUUGGGGAAAUCUGAGCAGCACCCUGUGAUCAUAAUCUCUGACAUCUGCCCUGUAUGCUGUACUGUGAUUUUGAAAAAAGAAAAAUUAUUAUAUUCAUGGAAUAUUAACUAAAGACAAAACUACAAAUAAAACAUCCAUUAUAUAGUAGUGACAAUCCUCCUUUCCCAACUAGACUAUCAGUUCCAAGAGUCUAAGGCAUUUUGUUUCUUUUUGUUCAUUGCUGAAUCCAAAGCUCCUAGAACCGUCUUGGAGUAGUCAGAGCUCAAUGAAUAUUUGGUGAAUAAGUGAAUGAAUAACACCUAUGGAAAUCCACAGAUCUUAACAGUAAAAACAUAAUAAGCAUUAAAAAUCUAAAUGUCAGAAGUAAACUUUAGAAUCAAUUCAAGUUUGAUCAUAUGAAUGAGUGAAACUGAAGUGGAAAUAAUCCCCCAAUAAAAAAAAUAAUUCAUAGAUGUUUAUUACAAACUUCAAACUUAACAAAACUUUUAAAAAAGUUAAUGAGCUGCAAACUGAGGAAAUAACUCUAAAAGAGCAUACCCAGAUUUAAAUUAAUAAUUUUGUAACUUCACUAUCCCAAAACAAUGGCAGUACUGUAAAAACAUCAUAGGGAGUUCAAUGGUGUGAGUGAUGCAAGACUCAGGAAUGAAAAUGAGCUUGGAUUUCUUCACUUCCUUUAGCCUGACAAUUAUAAAGGGUCAAAGUGGAAGAAAUGUACAAAUAAACAUCACUGUGUUCCUACUAAUAUAUUUAGUGUGUCUAUAUGUUCAGGUGGUAUUGAUGACCUUAUUUUACACUUUAAAUUUUUAUUAAAACAUCUUUUGCUCCCUCUGCUGUUUCCCAGCAGUAAACCCAGAGAACCCCAAUCCCAGAGUUACUAUUUUAUUUUAGAAUAGUGGAAAAACAAAGCUCUUGCUCACGGUCUUAUUCUGGCUGAAGUAAUACCAAAACAACCAAGUUCAUCGUGGUCUCAAACAAAAGAGGAAAACUUAGUCUUUACCAAUGAGGCUACGAUGGCAAAUUUGCCCCGAAUCUUUUAAGGGGGUAUUAACACACCCUUCCAUUACAAUAAAUUUUUUGAAUUACUGUAUAGUUGUUUUAUGAAAAGUGAUUGGAACAAUUGACUCCCAAGUUUAAGUAUCUUGGAAAAAGAGCAUGAGACUUUCAGUCUCCAGGAUAAGGGUUUCCUCCACCUCUGUGAUUCCUGCUGCACUUUGAGACAGAACCCACAGAAAUCUUCAAAAAUAUUAACUCUCCGUCCAGGUCAGCAUGCCCAGGAGGUCACGUCCCACUUCCCAGCUCUUGUCCCACUUCCUAACACUUGUCUGCGCGAAGCAGUAGCAGUCAGAACCAGGCACCAGAGCGCCCCCUGAAGGUAGACCGGGGAGCGGGGCCUCAGACAUAUCAGCCCGUACCUGGCCAGACAGUUUUCCUCCGCCGCGCAUCUCAGGUUGUACAUGGACAUCUUCUGCACGUACGUGGACGCCUGGAUGUAGUAGGGGUCGGCCACCAGGUCUGGGAGACCUAAACGUCAGCAGGCGACGGGCGCAGCAGUGAAACAACCCGGCGCCCCCCGCUCCAACUCCCUACCCCUCUAGGUCCCUUACUCCUCACCCUUCGCCCACCGGGACUGCAGAGUGGAGCGGAGGACAGCAAGAGAACUGGGGACGCCCGGGACUGCAAAGCAAUGUGAAAAGGAAGCAGGAGGGGCCAGACGCGCGGUUUGCACUGGAUUCCAGGGCUGCCACUGCAGGCGCGUGGGGGAGGGAUCGGAUCUGCGAGGACCGGGGCCCGCCGCGCCCAGGCAGCCACGUCGAGAAGCCACAUAGCUGGGGACCAGGUGCACGGGUGCUUCCAGCGGACUUGGGGGUACUUACCGUACUGGAAGUAGCCAGUGCCGUAUCCGGGCCGGUACCUGCCCCCAGGUCUGGGCCUUUCAUAAGUAUCGUAGUAGUUGUAAUAAGGGUUGUCGUCAGAGUACUUGUAGGGGUUGUAAGGGUCGUCGCCCACCAUGCCGUCCACGCGGCUGGGCGGCCGCAGGUUACUGAGCGCAGGAACUUCUCCCGGCGCUGUCUGGUUCUCCGCGCGCGAGGCGCCAGCUUCGCGGGCUCUAGAUGUCGAGUAGCCAGCUUGGAACCAGUGACGGGCGGUGGGCCUGGGGCGGCCAGCGGUGACUCCAGAUGAGCCGGCCGUCCGCGUUCGCGCCGCGGCGGUGCGGUUGUCGCGGAUCAGCAGGAUCGGAGUGCGGGGCUGCUGGGCGGAGGCGUUGGCUGCACCAGGGACGGCGGCGCCCGGGUCCCGGCGGCGCUGAGGCUGGUACUGUGAGCCCAGGCUCAGCAAGCUGAACACCUGCCCGUUGUUCUCCCAUUGGAUCUGCUGGCGCCAGGCGCCCGGAGCCGCCGGCGGCUCGCGCGGGGGCUGCUGUUGGCCGGCGGCGGGAGGGGCGCAGUGCACUAGCGCGCAGAGCUGCAAAGGCCCGAGCAGGAGCACGGUCCAGGCGAAGCGCAUCACUCCUUUUGCCAGAUUGACCCCGCUCGAGGAGGACGUGGCUCACAGAAAAUAAAAACGGGGCUCAAAUCACGUGAGGGAAGGAGAAAUCUUCAACCAAGGAGGCGAGCGGAGCACGGGUAUCUCAGUCUCCACCAAGCAAUGCCAAGGGUGGGAUUCAGACCCUUCCCCAGUCAAGGCGGCUGCUCGGACGUGGCACCCUUCCCUUUCCCCUUUCUCAGUCCUGGAAGGCAACGGGGAGCGGCGCGGCAGUCCCGGAGAGCGGGCAGUGUCUGGAGUGAAGGAAGGAGGAGAGAUUUUAAACUUUCUGGCACGUUUGCAAAGUUACACAAGCCGUUCUGGCCCGGCCGCCCCUCAGCUAUUUGUUCACGUAAUGCGAUUGGAAACGUGCAAGGCGGACAGCUCCUCGCCUCUGCCCCUCCCUCUCUCCCGUCCCUGCCCUCCUCCCCCCAGACACGUUGCACAGGGAGCGUUAAGGGGAAAGAACAAAACGGAACACACAUCCUGAGACACACUGGCUUAAUCUGGGGCGAACAUGCAGGAAUUUCAAAAAACUCAGACAGGCGAAGGCAGCCAGGCCAUGGGGCGACGCCAAAAUAUGCACGAAGAAAAAUGCUAUUAGGUCACCAGCCCUUGAGAGGCGGGAAGUCGGGAGGUUGGGAGGGUGCUGGGGGUGAGAGGGGGGCGGGGGAGGAUUGUGACUAAAGUUUAUCCAUAAAAGAGUUAACCAGACACAUUUCCCAACGCACACUCUCUCGCUUUUAUGGGAAGCGCCCUCAGCAAAUAAACCCCAGGAUAUCAAAUUUUGUUUUUCUGUGUGUAGGUAAUAUGAGAAAUGGGUUACAAAUUUAUUUCCUACAGUGAAUAUUUUAAUAACCAAAAGUGAAAUUGUACAGGGAACAAAGCCAGCUAACGCUGCAGCUAUGAAUAAACCUGUCUCUUUUUCAAAA